CUCCCGCUCCUCCUCGGCCUCCCCUUCGGGCGCUCUCGCGCUAACUGUGCUCCUCCGGGGCCCUCCGCCUGCUCCCAGCCAUGGUGGCCUGGCGCUCGGCGUUCCUUGUCUGCCUCGCUUUCUCCUUGGCCACCCUGGUCCAGCGAGGAUCUGGGGACUUUGAUGAUUUUAACCUGGAGGAUGCAGUGAAAGAAACUUCCUCAGUAAAGCCUGCCUUAGGAAUGUACCACAAACUAGAUGGCUUAAAACAACAGAACUUUAUUCUGUCACUGUUCUGGAUGCUAGAAGUUCUAUAUCAAGGAUCACUGUAAGGAUGACAUGGGAGGAGCCAUGUGAAGCACUCAGCACAGUCCUUGGAACAAGUGCCAGGUUGAUAGUUGUGGAACCAAGGCUUGGAGCCCUCAAGGAUCAUGCUCAGGCUGUGGAACUCCCUGGACCACGUGCCAUCUCCAGCAGAUCUGGGUGCAAGCCCAGGUUCACUAAUCACCAGGUCACAUGUGAGACCAUGUCCACCUCACCACCCUCAGCCUCCAAAGAAAAAGCCAUGGGACCACACCACCACCACCACAACCAAUAGGCCAGGAACCACCAGAGCUCCGGCAAAACCUCCAGGUAGUGGAUUGGACUUGGCUGAUGCUUUGGAUGAUCAAGAUGAUGGCCGCAGGAAACCGGGUAUAGGAGGAAGAGAGAGAUGGAACCAUGUAACCACCACGACCAAGAGGCCAGUAACCACCAGAGCUCCAGCAAAUACUUUAGGAAAUGAUUUUGACUUGGCUGAUGCCCUGGAUGAUCGAAAUGAUCGAGAUGAUGGCCGCAGGAAACCAAUUGCUGGAGGAGGAGGUUUUUCAGACAAGGAUCUUGAAGACAUAGUAGGGGGUGGAGAAUACAAACCUGACAAGGGUAAAGGUGAUGGCCGGUACGGCAGCAAUGACGACCCUGGAUCUGGCAUGGUGGCAGAGCCUGGCACCAUUGCCGGGGUGGCCAGCGCCCUGGCCAUGGCCCUCAUCGGUGCCGUCUCCAGCUACAUCUCCUACCAGCAGAAGAAGUUCUGCUUCAGCAUUCAGCAGGGUCUCAACGCAGACUACGUGAAGGGAGAGAACCUGGAAGCCGUGGUAUGUGAGGAACCCCAAGUGAAAUACUCCACGUUGCACACGCAGUCUGCAGAGCCGCCGCCGCCGCCCGAACCAGCCCGGAUCUGAGGGCCCUGUCCAGCUGCAGGCAUGCACAAUGGUGCCACCGCUUGUCACCCGGCUCCCCCCACCCCUUCAUUUGGACCCGCAGCUGCUGUGCUGCUCUGUGCCAUCGGCUCCUUGUUGGUCUGAGUUUCCCGGAUGAGCUCUGGGUGUUUGUGAGUUUGGUUUCUCUGCCCUGCCCCAAGCGUGCUGAGACUUGGUGCCGAAAUUCAAGAGCCAGCUCUGAUAGAAAGCCAGCACCAGCCUCGGGAGCUGCUGAGCCACCAACUCCCAAAGCCAGCCUGCCUCCAGCUUUACUGAGCACAGGAUGCGGGGGCCAAGAUGAUGCUGAGGCCUGAUGACAUUUAUGCUUAGGGGACAAGAGUUUGAACUCAAGGGACUGUGACCCCUGCACACUGGAGUGGCUCAUUGUGGCAGGUUUCUGCCAAUAGACAGCCCCUGACAGUGGCCUCAAGGAGCUGCAGGUGGGGGGCUCAGCCUGCACCCACUUGGAGCCCCUGCAAGGAGCGAACCGGUCAGCACCAAGUAACACCACACACACGCAGCACCCAGGAUGAUGGUUUCACUUCAGUCUUCCCCAUCCCAGGUUUUAUGUUGCUGGGCUUCCGGAGAGCCGGUCCAAGCGGAGGCUUUCAGUGAUUUAAGUACAAACAUGCAUCUCGUGAUAGUCCUGCCUUGAGAGCUUAGGAAUCUUCCGGAUAAGUAUGAAGCAAUUCGUAGGCCUGUUUCCCAUCUGAUUCCAUAGGGGGCUGGGUGUGGCCUUCGGGUUGACAUGAGAAAGGUCUUUAGCAAUCAUUUCUGCACCGGAGAUGAGUUUUAUCCUGUGUUGGGGAGAGGUGCUCACCCUCCACCCUGUGUCCCUGUUUUGGUAGCAAGAGUGACCGAUGUCAAGAACGAGCAUCAAAGCCAGAAUCCUGCUUGUUUGCUUAAAAAUGUAAUUGGGGGCGGCGGGGGAGGAGAGGGGAAAGAGACAUUCGCUUGGUUUAGUGAAACGCAGGUGACUUUGUAGCUCUGUGGUCAGCCUACUUGUCUGCUCUGAGGGAGAGUGCGUGGGGAGCCAUGCUCACCGUGGCAAACACAGGAACCCCAUGACUCGCCCCUCACCUGGCGUGGAGCUGCCUGGUUUGGGCUGGAGCAGAGCUGGUUUCCUGGAAUGUUCCUUUGGCCCACAUAUGGUUCUGUCCCGGUGAGCUCUGUUGUCAGAGGCUCACGGGACAGAACCACAUGCUAGGGUCUAGGGCCCCUGUCUACUGAUAGUCAGUUUGCUGUGUCAGAAAGCACUUCUGAAAGCAGAUAUGAGUCACCAGACAGGCAGGAUCUUACAAAACUCACGGGCCUCUUUGGUCUGCAUGAUGGCCCCAUGCGUUUCAUAGGCUGUCCACUGAGCGGGAUUGUCUGCUGAGUGGGAUGAGCCAACUCCAGUUUCUUAAGGAAACCACUGGAAUCUGCAGCCCCCACAUGCAUCUGUCUAACGCAUGCCUCGUGUUCGUUUUGCAAACAUGCCUGUGGUGGAGGGUGGUCAGUUGUAGCCCUGUGCGUCUCAAGGCUGCCUUGUGAGGCCAUUCCCAGUGCGUGCCCUUGAGCUCCUUACCACCCCUUUUCCUGCUCGGCCCUUUAAUCCCUGACAGACCUGGACUGUGUGGCUGAAGGGGGACCUGCAGCACUGCAGAAAUGCCUCUGCGUGGUGCCAUGAAGGAAAGAAACCUUGGCCUGGUCUCGAGAAGCUUCCCAUGCUUCAGGAAGUUAGUAAGGGUGGGGUGGCUUGCAGGAUUGGCCUGUUUCCAGGGCCUCCCACACUCAUUGGCCAGAUUGUGAACUUUGUCAGGCUUGUCCCUCCCUGAUACCAAGUAUGUCGAGAACCGAUGGCCCCACCCUCUGGCUGGUGCUGGGCCGGAGGUGGCUAUGGAGGAUUUUGGCAUGCGUGGCCUGUCGCCACCUGGACAGCGUGACCUCAGGGGUUGUCCACUUUACCUUUAUGGUGAGGCCUGUCGGAUGGCUAAGUCCUUGAAACCCUAGAGCUGUGACGUAGAAUAUGUGCUGUCUGUGAGACCGUGUUCCCAGGAGCACUGACUGCAGUUGAGAGAGACCCAUUUUGCUCUCCCUUACCGCCCCCCGCCCCGGGUGCUUUCUGCACAAAGCCUAGAGCCUGGCACUCAAGCCCACCGGUGGCAGCUCCUAGUGACUGGACAUGCCUGGAAGACCCCUCAGCCUUCUGUUUGCAGAACGUUCAUUUCAGGAGCUUCUCCUUCCCACAGACAUCUUACACUUGCUCGACACUGCCACCUGCAGAAGCCUGGCGGGCUCUGGUCACCAUGUGUCUAUCUGAAGGUUGCACUGGCCAGCAUGGGCCUGUCCCAAGCGAGAGGGGAGACACAGUGGACUGAAAGGACUGGUUGAAAGUGGCCAAUCUCUAUCAGCUUAAUUUGGCAGAGAAAAUUUGUAACAACUCUGAGCACAUGCUGGGUGAAGUCACAGCUCAAGGAAAGAUAAAGCUGGGCGGAAGGAGGUGUGCGUGGCUUCUGGGGUGGGACCCAGAGGGGAGGCUCUGGGACAGGGGCUGGGGUUCAGUGCCAGGGCCCUGAGGAAGAAAUGGGGACUGAUCUCAAAAUUCCAGAAUUCCCUGUACAUCUGUUCACGUGCUUGUGUCCAGGUGUGACUUGUAAACUGUCUAGUGUUUGCAUUAAAUAAAAUGGCACCGAGCAGA